CUGCAUCCGGGCCUGAGAGUGCAGGCUUGAGGGAAGCAUGGAGGUCCAUGGCAAGCCCAAGGCUAGCCCGAGUUGUUCGUCGCCCACCCGGGAUUCCUCAGGAGUCCCAGUGUCCAAGGAGCUGCUGACGGCGGGAAGCGACGGCCGCGGAGGUAUAUGGGACAGGUUGCUCAUCAACUCCCAACCUAAGUCCAGAAAGACCUCCACUCUUCAAACAGUUCGGAUAGAGAGGAGUCCCUUAUUGGACCAGGUACAGACAUUUCUCCCACAGAUGGCACGGGCAAAUGAAAAGCUAAGAAAAGAAAUGGCAGCUGCACCACCUGGUCGUUUCAAUAUUGAAAACAUUGAUGGGCCUCAUAGUAAAGUUAUACAAAUGGAUGUGGCUUUGUUUGAGAUGAAUCAGUCGGAUUCAAAAGAAGUGGACAGUUCAGAAGAGAGUUCACAAGACAGUUCAGAGAACAGUUCAGAAUCAGAAGACGAAGAUGACAGCAUCCCAUCUGAAGUCACCAUAGAUAACAUUAAGCUUCCCAAUUCUGAAGGUGGAAAAGGCAAGAUUGAAGUUUUGGACAGUCCAGCAAGUAAAAAAAAGAAAUAGUCAAAUAAAUUAUCUGAAAAGAAACAGGUGACAUAUGUCUGCAAAUUCUGUGAAAAAGAAUGUGAUUCACGGGUUCUUUUGCUUUUCAGGCACCUAUGGUGCUUUUAUAUGUUAAAAACUUUAGACAAGUUAAAUUUGACAGAGUUUCUUUGGGCAAAGAAUGAUUAAUGAGUUAGGUAGCAUUGUAAACUGAAAGGGGUUCAGAGACCUCCGCUCUACAGCAAGGAAAGUGUGCUUUUAUCAGCUGAACACAGAAGUAGAGUACAGGAAUAACUUGAUGGGUUACAGCUAGGUGUUUGCCUAAAUAAGGCAAAGAGGAGACCUAAGGCUGCCUGAUGUCCCAUAGGUAUGGUCUGAUCUAAGGAGAUCUAAGGCUGCCUUGUCCGAUGGGCUGAGGCUUGGCUGUUUGUGAUUGGCCAGACUUGGCUAUUUGUUAUAAAAAUACACUCCUGAGUUAGGUUUUGGUGUGUAGAGUACAGGAAUAACUUGAUGGGUUACAGCUAGGUGUUUGCCUAAAUAAGGCAAAGAGGAGACCUAAGCCCAGCAUGUCGUCCACUGUUUGGGAUGCCUGCAAACUAACCAUUAGCUCCUCCUGCAAACAUCAUGUGUUCUGUUCCCUUGAGAAAUUUCUUUCAUGCAUAUGGUGGCAGUGUCCAAAGAAACAAUAGUGUCAGCUACAAAUUGUAUUGAAUUUUCUGUAGUAGCAAAAUCUGGAAAAAUAGGUACAACAUUCAGUUUUGUUUAGCACCAUACAUAACCCCCAACAUGAGCAAAGAGGAGAUCUAAGGCUGCAUGAUAUCCCAUUAAGUGCUUUUGUUAAAUGCUUUCAGAGGGUGGCUCCUACCCCAGGAGGUCUGGUUGGUCAUAAAAUAAGAUUUUUCCCUAUCUGUGCAUUAGUUUUAAAUUCCAUAUGACUAGCACCCAACCACUACAAAGAGUGAGUCCCCAGGAGCCCCACUGUAAUCUUUCCUCAGUGGAAACUAGCAUAUCUUUUUUUUUUUCGAGAUGGAGUCUUGCUCUGUUGCUCAGGCUGGAGUGCAGUGGCGCGAUCUCAGCUCACUACAAGCUCUGCCUCCCGGGUUCACGCCAUUCUCCUGCCUCAGCCUCCUCAGUAGCUGGGAGUACAGGCGCCCACCACCAUGCCCGGCUAAUUUUUUUUUUUUUUGUAUUUUUAGUAGAGACGGGAUUUCACCGUGUUAGCCAGGAUGGUCUCAAUCUCCUGACCUCGUGUUCCACCCUUCUUGACCUGCCAAAGUGUUGGGAUUACAGGCAUGAGCCACCGUGCCCGGCUGGAAACUAGCUUAUCUUUAUUUUCUUCAUCUAUUCCAAGGUUGGUGCAAAUUUCAAUUGCUGACCAUUUUAGACUCUGAUAAUAGGAGGUAUUUAUGGGGACUUUUGGGGAAGCUAUUUGGAAGGCAGGAUUGAACCAUGCCAAAUAGCAAGAUCCUAACCAGUGGGGAGCAAAAUGGAGUAAGCAUAUUUUCUGUAGACCAAUACAGGCAGACCCUCUGAGGCUGGAAAAGAGGGCUACCUAGUGGUAUUUGAGCAUCAGUCAGUUCAGUUCAUCCACUGGUACAUCUGCAUAGCUCCUGAACAAGGUCCAGGAGGAAACUUACUUUUUUAUAGUUCCCCUCCUUUUAAAAAGAUGUUUUACAUUUUAUUAUUUUCAUUUUUUUUUUUUUUAACUUUUAGGUUCAGAGGUACAUGUGGAGGUUUGUUAUAUAGACAAAUUGGGUAUUGUGGGGGUUUGGUGUACAGAUUAUUUCAUCACCUGGUGAUAAGCAUAGUGCCCAAUAGGUAGUUUUAAAUCUGCACCCUCCUCCCACCCUCCAUCCUCAAGUGGGCCCUAAUGUCUGGUUCCCUUCUUUGCAUCCAUGUGUACUCAACGUUUAGCUCCCACUAAUAAGUGAGAACAUGUGGUAUUUUUCUGUUCCUGUGUUGGUUGCUUAGGUCCUGAUCAUCUGUGUUAGCUUUCUGCCUUGAUGAUCUGCCUAAUACUGUCAGUGGGGUGUUAAAGUCUCCCACUAUUAUCUAGCUCUCUUUGUAGGUCUCUGAAUGCUUGCUUUAUGAAUCUGGGUGCUUCUCUGUUGGGUGCAUGUAUGUUUAGGAUAGUUAGGUCUUAUUGAAUUAAGCCCUUUAUCAUUAUGUAAUGCCCUUCUUUGUCUUUUUUUAUUUUUGUAAAAGUAUGUUUUGUCUGAAAUUAAAAUAGCAACCCCUGCCUUUUUCUUUCUGUUUGCUUGGUAGAGUUUUCUCCAUCCCUUUACUUUGAGCUUCUGAGUGUCACUGCAUGUGAGGUGGGUCUCUUGAAGAUAGCAUACCAUUGGAUUUUGCUUCUUUAUCCAAGUUGCCACACUGUUUCUUUUGAUUGGGGCAUUUAGCCCAUUUACAUUCAAGGUUAGUAUUGAUAUGUGUGCAUUUGAUCCUGUCAUCAUAUUGUUAGCUGGUUACCAUGCAGACUUGUCUGUGUGGUUGCUUUAUAGUGUUACUAAUCUACCUACUUAAGUGUGUUUUUGUAGCGGCUGGUAACCCAGUCUUUCCUUUAUAUAGUUAGCACUCCCUUCCAAAACUCUUGUAAGGCAGAUCUGAUGUUAACAAAUUCCCUUAGCAUUUGCCUGUCUGAAAAGGAUCUUAUUUCUCCUUUGCUUAUGAAGCUUAGUUUAGUCAGAUAUGAAUUCUUGGUUGAAAAUUAUUUUCUUUAAGAAUGCUGAGGGUGUGGCACACCAGCAUGGCACAUGUAUACAUAUGUAACUAACCAGCACAUUGUGCACAUGUACCCUAAAACUUAAAGUAUAAUAAUAAAAAUAAAUAAAUAAAGAAUGCUGAAUAUAGGCCCCCGAUCUCUUCUGGCUUGUAGAGUUUCUGCUGACAGUUCUGCUGUUAGCCUGAUGGGUUUCCCUUUGUAGGUGACUUGCCCCUUCUCUCUCACUGCCUUUAGCAUUUUUUCUUUCAUUUCCACCUUGGAGGAUCUGAUGACUGUAUGUUUUAGGUUGGUCUGCUUGUGUAGUAUUUCACAAGGGUUUUCCGCAUUUCCUGAAUUUGAAUGUUGGCCUCUCUAGCAAGGUUGGGGAAGUUUUCAUCAGCGAUAUCCUGAAAUAUGUUUUCAAAGUUGCUUGGUUUCUCUCCCUUUCAGUCACAUCAAUGAGUCAUAGAUUGGGUCUCUUUUCAUAAUCCCAUAUUUCUCGGAAGUUUUGUCCAUUCUUUAUUGUUUUUUUUCUCCAAUAAAGAAAAAGAUGUUUCAGAGAGCCAUCUUCAAGCUCUGAGAUUCUUUCCUCAGUUUGGUCAAUUCUGCUGUUAAUACUUGUGAUUGCAUUAUGCAAUUCUUGUAGUGUGUUUUUCAGCUCUGUCAGAUCGGUUUAGUUCUCUCUUAUAAUGGCCGUUUUGUUUAUCAGCUUCUGUAUCAUUUUAUUGUAAUCCUUAGAUUCCACGGAUUGGGUUUGACUUUAUCCUGUAUGUUGAUGAUCUUCAUUCCUGUCUAUAUUCUGAAUUUUAUUUCUGCCAUUUCAGCCAUCUCAGCCUGGUUAAGAACCAUUGCUGGGGAACUAGUGUAGUUUUUUGGAGGUAAGAAGAUACUCUAGUGCUUUUGUCAGUUUUUGCACUGAUUCUUUUUUAUCUUUGUGGGCUCAUGUCGCUGAAGUUGCUAUCCUUUGGAUGAUUUUUUUUCUUUUAUCCUACUUUAUGUCCUUGUGUGUUUAAUUGUGGUAUAAAGUGGGUUUAGUCAACUGGCUUCAUUUCUAGAAGGUUUUCAGGGGCCAAGGCUCAACUCAGGAUUCCUGGACUGUAUGCUGUAAUUCUGGGGGGCUGAUAUCAGGCCCCUGGCUUUGUUCUCUGGCCACUGGAGGUUAGGUACCUGCUGUGCUAGAGGGGCCAAGAUAUUUCUGGACCACUGGUCAGAACACUUCAAUGGGUGGUGCCAGCCAAAGUGCUUUGUAUGGCAGUGGCAGUGGGAUCUGUCCUCAUAUGCACAUGCCAGCAAUAGCAGUGGGGUGCGGUGCACACUCAUCAGCUUCAGAGGGGUGCUGGCAGUUGCAAGGGUGCUGUUUUUGUGCAGGCAUUUGUAGUGGCUGUGGUGUUAGCAUGGGGGUGGGGCGCUGUGGCUGCUGCUAGAUUUUGUGUGCCCUCUGUGCGUGUGCUUACAUGGGUAGCAGUGGCCACUCAGGGUAAGGGGGCGGGCUGCUGGUCUCCAUGCAUAGUUUCACACCACUGGCAGUGUUGACACAGGGGCAGGGUACUGGUGGCUGCGGGACUGGUGCCAAAUGUGCGCACGUUUAUGCUGGCUGCAGUGGCUGCACAGGGCGCAGGGCAGGUCCACUGGUCACUGUGCCUAGUUUUGCAGCUGGUGGCAGUGUUGGUGUCGGAGUGGGGUACUGGUGGUCUCCGUACCUGCAGAUACUCCAGUGGCAGUGGCAGCAUGGUGGUCGGGUGCAGUGUGCUCAAGCCAGCAGUAGUGGCAUGGCCAGGUGCACAUGUACCCACACACUGGCAGGAAAUUGGAGGCGAGGUCUGUGUACACAGGUGCUGGCAAAGUGAUUCGGGGGUUGGCUGCAUGCCAGCGUCUGCAGGCAAGGUGCCAUGGGGGAGUCUGCAGUGGGAGGAGAGAGUGGGAUCAGGUGGUCUGGUGCACGGUCUGUUGUGGGUGGGGGUAGUACUGGAGUUCUCUGCCAUUCAGGCACGAUCUGCCAACUCAGGUGCUAUAGCGUAGGCCCCCAGGACGCACCCCACCUGGGCAUCUAAGGCUGCACUGCAAGCAGGGACAGCCAGGCUGAGGCCCAGGGAGAGGUCAGGAAACUGAGGAGUGCUUAGUUCCGAUCGGCCAGGUCUCAUAGGCAAGACUGCCCUGCAUUUUUCAAGUCUGAUAGUUCCUCUAGGGUUGAAGUCUCUUAGGGGAGCAAGGUGAGUCAUGGGUGAUGGGCGUCCCUGGCCAUGAUCCACUACAGAUGCUCCCGCACCAAAGCCUCUGGGCUCUGCACCAGCUAGAAUUCUGCCCUACCACUUCUCUAAGCAGCUCUCCCUGCAAGCUCAAGAGUCCAUGGGGGUCCUGGGGUCUCCUGCCAGAUUCCAGAGGCCUGUGGUGGGAGUCAGUUGCUGCUUGCCUGCUCAACUCACCCCUUUUCCAGGAGUCGGGGGCCAGGAACGAGUCUUAGUGUGUGGUAGCCCCUUGCAGGGUUCCCCGCUUCCUCCCUCUUCAGCCCAGCAUCUGUGUCUUCCCUUCAUCCACUCUCAGUGCCCUCCCUCUGAAGAUCUGCUGGGAGUGCACCAGUCUUCCUGAUAUCCCAGUCUCUUGGUGGCAGAUGUUCCUUCUGGCUGCAUCUAGCUGAUCAUCUUGCCUCCAACCUGUUCCCUUUAUAGCAUAAUGUGUAUAACCACAUUUAGUGGAAAAGCACCUUACUAUAUUUAAUCCAAUGACAUUAUACAAAUAAUCACCGGUGCCCACAUAGAUAGUCCCCAAGUCUUGAGUAUGUGAUACCUGGAAGCAUAAUAUACCUUUUGUAGGCAUCACUUGGUUUGAUGUUCUAUAUUUGAUAGUGGUUAGGUUAUUAAUUGGAAAGGUUGGGAUAUUCCUUUCAGUGAGUGUAGGCAAGCAAAUAGCAGUGACAUUUAGAACAUCAAGGAUUGCUUUCUCUUCCUUUGGGGUUUCAGGGUAAUUCUCUUCGGGAACUCAGAGAGGUGUUGGCAUUAGUGGAGUUGUUUCCUGGUUUUUACCCAUUAGCCCACAAACCCAAACAGUUGCUCUGUUUUUUCUGCUAGAGCAUGAGCCUUACCUAAAGCCAUUGCAAAUUAUGGUCCUAUGGAUUUUCCUGUAAGGAAAAGGAAAGAUUAAGACAAUAGGAAAUAAGGGAAAAAGAAAAGGGACAUAGUUAUCAUGAUGACAGAGAAGAGAACUCUUGAUCCAUGAUCAAAUUCUUACCACCCAUACUGCAGCAAAAGUCUUGAGGGUCUGAACUUUUGCUGCAGUGUGGAUGGUAAGAAUUUGGUAUGGUCCCUUCCAUAGGGGUUUGAGGGCAGUGUUUCACUGAUGUUGUUUUCAGAAGACCCAAUCUCCAUGUUCCAGAUUGUGAAAUGCUUGGUUGUCCUCCAUUGAUAGAUCGUGAAAGGCUUUUUUUUUAACCUGGUGAAAAUAUACUUUGGCAUAAUACAUUAAGGCCUUGCAGUAUUUAGUCAUGUCAGUUUACAGGAGCAGGAGAUAUAUGAGGUUUAAUUAUUAGGGGCAUAGGUUUUUCAGUAACUAUUUCAUAAGAAACUAAUUUAUUUUGUAUUUUCUGUUGGGGUGGAUCUAGUUGCCCAUAAGGCCAAUGGUAAUACCUUUGGACGAGGCAAUUCAAUCAAUUCAGUUAACUUUACCAAUUUCAGUUUAAAGUUUCAUUUGUUCUUUUGAGCUUUCCAGAAGAUUAAGGGUGUUAGGGAUGAUGGUAAUACCAUUGUGUUCGAUUAACUGUUUUAGCUGUUUUAUAACUUGUCCAGUGAAACAGGUUCUUCUAUUGCUGGAAAUUCCUCCAGGGAAGCCCCAGAAGGAAACAUACUUUCUAAUAACUUAUUGUCAUAGCAUUGGCCUUCCUACAUGAUAAAGCUUCUAUCCGUCUAGAGAACACAAAGACUUUUAUAAGAACAUAUUGUUAUCCCAUUAAGGGUGGCAAUUGAUGAAAUCCAUCUGUAAACAUUCAAAUGGUCCAGGAGGCAGUAGAAAUGUACCACCUAAAAUUUGGAUUAUCUUUCCAGGAUUAUGAGCUUGAUAAACCAAACAUUAGUUAUAAGCCAUUUUAGCAAUUUUAGAAUAGUCAUCCCACCAAUAUUUUUUCAAUUUCUGCCUUUAGAGAGCAUAACAGUUCUGGUUCAGGAGAGUCAGGAAACUCUAAGAUUAUUUGUCCCUCUGAAAGAGAAUUUUAUAUGCCCUUUUGCCUUGGAGAGCAAGUCUUGCCCCAGCAGAUUUACUGGGGCAGUAUCACAUAAUUAAAAAGUAUGAUUUUCUGUAAAUGACACCAGUGUCAGUUGGAUGGCUUCCAGUAUGGGAACCUUUUCAACUUGAUUUGAAACCCUACCACAGAAAUAAUGUUUCCACAGAGUAAACAUUUUUACUCUGAGGGAUGUAUUAGCUUAUUAAGGUAGAGUUUAUAGUAGAUGAAAGUGGCUCUAGUAUCCACCAGAAUUGUAUAAGAUUUUUCAUUUGUUUUAACUUUUGUUUUUCCAUGUUUAUUUCUUUUCUUUUUUUAAUAGUACUUUGAGUUGCUGUUUAUCCAUGUUUAUUUAAAGGUAUUAUGGGGAGCAGUUUUCUGGAGAAUUCCUUGGAUGCUCAUCAAUGUUGAUUAUUAUCUCUAGAGUUAAGACCUUGUGGACUCAUUCUAGUGGGGAAAUAGUAUGGCCCCAAGGAAGGAGGCUUACUGGUAUACUGAAAUAAGAAUGCAAAAUCUCUUUUCCAGCAUCCUAGUUGUUUGCAAUGAAGGGAGACACCUUAGGGCAAAUAAUUUCUUGGUCUAAGAUCUCUUGGUUUUAGCUUAAAAUAAGGGAGAGGAAGUCCCUUUGGUCUUGGUCUUUGUGGUUAUUGUAAUUAGAGAGACAUGAGCUUUUCGACCUUUAGUCUUUUACUUACUCUAUUCUCUCAAAAUGUUGGGCUAGGGCCACCAAUUCAAUCAUAUCUAUAACCUCCCAUCCUGGUUUGUGUUUUUUAUUCAGGUUACUAAGUUCAGGAUGAGCUCCAUUUACAAAUAGAGCAGUUAAUCCUGUUUCAGGCACUGCCAGAAGUAUCCCUUGGUGUAUUGGAACCUGGAAUGUUUUACAAAUAGUCUUUCUGAAUGGACCCUGUAAUCUGAAACUGGUUCAUUCUAUUUUUUGUCUAUGAGAUUGUAUGAUGGACCAAUCAAUUUUUUGUAGCAAAAUCUUAGGAAUUGAAUUUUAAAGGUUUUCAACAAUUUUUCUAGGUCUCAUUGGCCCUACUCUUGAUGAGGUUUUGGGGGAGUCUUUAAUAUCCUGAUUAAGUUUUUCCCAUUCUCUUGUCAUACAUUUUCAAGCUUUGCCAUGUCCCAGUAUCAUAUGAAUAAAUUGGUCAGAGAGUCCUGGCUUGUAAGCUCCUGUGCAAAUUCUAAAAUCUUCAGUACAUUUUUGAGUGUUUUCCCUGGGCUAGGGAAGUCUUUUACCGUGUCUGGAAGCUUAAUUUUUGACCAUGGAGUAAAGGUGGUUAUGGCAGGCAGGCCUGGCUGAUCAGAGAAUCCCAUUUUGUAAGGCAUUUGUCUAACUUGCCUUUUCUCAUUAUCUUUAGAAUGAAAGAGUAGUUGAGCAAAAAGGUUAUUAGACUCAGAGUAUUGAGGUAAAGAUGGGUAAAGAGAAAGAACAAAACAGGUUUGAAUCAGUCAAGAUACAGUCUUUUUUUGUAUCAUCCUUAAGCUACUUAAGGUUUUCAUUUGCCUUCUGUAAGGAAUCUUUUACUACCUGUAUGUACCAAUUUAAAGAAUGCAUCUCAUUGCUUAUGAAGCAUUUUGGAUUCUUUCUUUUGUAGUGUGCCUUGCAAGUGAACAAGUUUAUGUAGGUUAAAACUUUCCCACUGUGGGCCACUGGAAUUCUAAUUUUUUUUGUGUGUGUGUGAGUUUCAUUUUUCUAGAAAAGCAACAUGCCCUGAGUCUGUAGUUCUUAUACACGAAAUUGGCUAUAGUUCCAGAUGGAGGAGUUCUAGACUCCAUGGAUCCAGAUGAACUCAUGAUUCCCUGUCUUCUUGUGACUUAUCAUAGGCCUUCUACUGGACCCAGUCUCUGGACCCUGUUUGGUAAAAGAAUUGUUCAAGUAAAUUUGGAGAGCUCAAAACACAAAUCUGUGUAGCUUUAAUCUGAAAGGGAAAUCACACACAACCUCCAGUUGCUGUGAGAGAGGAAUGGUUACAAUAGACCCAGCAAAUACAUUCAUUUGGUCACUAGGGUGCUCCUGGGCGGUUGUUGGAAGUCGCCUUUGGACGCCACUUCUGACACCAAAAACUUAAUUGUUAAAACCUCUAGACAAAUUAAAUUUAACAGUUUGUUUGAGCAAAGAACAAUUUUAUGAAUUAGCACUCAAAACUGAAAGGUUCAGAGUGUUCCACUCUGUGGCACAGAGAGUAUGCUUUUAUAAGUAUAAAUUGAACUUGGAAGUAAACUACAGAAAUAACUGGAUUGGUUACAGCUAGGCAUUUGCCCUAUUUGUGCAUGGUUUGAUAACUUGACUGCCUAUGACUGGCUGAAGCUCACCUGUUUCUGUCUGGCUUAAACCUAGCUAUUCGUUACAAAAGUAUUCUGCUAAGUUAGGUUUUGGUUUGUUUAUUACUGAGGUAGAUUGCAGUUUGUUAUAUAGGAACUACAAGUACCAAGGGAGUCUCAGGCUAAUGGCCUCCUGCUUAUUUAAUUUCACAUAUGUAAUAUUGGAUGUAUUUUGUUUCUCAGAGAAACCAGAGCUAGUUUUUAAAGAGUUGGGAUAUAUAGCAUUUGGAUGUCUUCCCAGGGUAGAAUGAUCUUUAUUCUCUUCUAUGGUAGAGUUUAGAAAGCUUAAUUUUGUGCAUGGUGAUGAGUGAAUUUGUUAGCAUCUUUUUUCUUCAGCAUGGAUUUCAGAAACAUCAAUUUUAUUUUAAAGUAAAAAUAAAGGCCAGGUGCGGUGGCUCACACCUGUAAUCCCAGCACUUUGGGAGGCCAAGGUGGGCAGAUCACGAGGUCAGGAGUUUGAGACCUGCCUGGCCAACGUGAAUCCCCGUCUCUACUAAAAAUAUAAAAAUUAGCUGGGCGUGGUGGCACGUGCCUGUAGUUCCAGCUACUUGGGAGGCUGAGACAGAAGAGUCACUUGAACCCAGGAGGUGGAGGUUGCAGUGAGCUGAGCUCACUGGAGGCUGGGUGACAGAGCAAGACUGUGUCUCAAAACAAAUAAAUAAAUAAAAAUUACCAGUUUUGUUUUAAAUUAUCUGUUUGAAUAAAAUAACCUAGUUUUUUUAGGUUAUUAUAAAGUCAAACUUGUCACCAUCAAGAUGGGUUUAAUGAGGGAGGAAUAUGUGAAAAAGAAAAAAGAUUUUUACAAAGAAAAGAAUUACUUAUACAGUUGAUCCUUGAACAAUGCAGGAGUUAGGGUGCUGACCCCCUUUGUGGUCAAAAAUCUAUGUAUAACUUUUGACUCCCUGAAAACUUAACUACUAAUAGCCUACUAUUGACUAGAAGCCUUAGUGAAACAUAAAUAGUUAACACAUAUUGUAUAUGUUAUAUGUAUUAUAUAUUGUAUUUUUACAAUAAAGUAAGCUACGGAAAAGAAAAUAUCACUAAGGAAAUCAGGAAGAGAAAUAUAUACUUACUGUUCUUUAAAUGGAAGUGGAUCAUCAUUAAAGACUUCAUCCUCAUUGUCUUCAGGUUGAGUAGGUUGAGGAGGAGGAAGCAGAGGGGUUGGCACAGGUGGAAGAGGUAUAGAAGAAGAAGGCAUACUCAUUGUAACUUUAUGGAAAUACAUUGUAAUUUCUGUCUGACUUUCUUACUUACUCAUUUUGUUACCAGUGGAGGGUCUUGACUCUGAGUUGUUUGACAAAGAAUUGGAUAAAACGUGCAAAUCAAUGAAAGGAUGAAGCAACAAAAGCACAGAUUUGUUGAAAUGAAAGUACACUUCACAGAGUGGGAGCAGGCUCAAGCAAGUGGCUCAAGAGUGCUGGUUAGAGAAUUUUCUGGGGUUUAAAUACCCUCUAGAGGUUUCCCAUUGGUUACUUGGUUUACACCCUAUUUAAAUGAGGUAGUGGUCUGCAGCCAGUCUGAUUAGUUGCUGGGUGACCAAUCAGAGGCUGAAGUGAAGUUACAGAGUUACACCCUAUGCAAACAUCUGAUUGGUUGUGGAAGGUGAAGUGAAGUUACAAAGUUGUAACCCUGCGCAAAGACUAGGCUUGUGACCAGUCUGAUUGGUUGCAGGAGGGGACCAGAAGUACUUGCCAUUUUUCAUCUGUGACACAGAAGCAGAGGAGCUGCAAAGGGAGAGCCUCUGAUCCUUUUGUUACUUGGGCGUGGAAAGUUGGGGUUUUCCUUUUGAUUCAGUCUAGGAAGUCAGUGCGAAUUGGCCUUAAGUUCCCUGCCUCCAGGCCCUAUUCUCCUGGCUCAGUUUCUCUAAAAAUAUGUCUAUACAGUACCAAUCUUCUACCAUUUGCUUUAGUUUUAGUGUGUGUAUCAUAGAAAGGUCCAUGUUAUAAAAGAAGUCAAAAGCAACCUUGAAUGAUCAGAACCCUUCUGCCAGAUUGUCUAAUGUCAAUGUGUUUUCUGAUACUGAUGCUUCUCCAUCUUCCUCAUCGUCUGGCACUGUGGCUCAGAAGCAUUCAUCUCCAUCAAGCUGUCUUCUGUUAAUUCCUCUGGUGUGAUGUCUGUUAGCUUUUGAAUUUCUCCAAGAUCCCUGUCUUGAAACCCUUCACUCCACCUGCCCCACCUUUUUUGCCACAUUCACAAUCUCUUUCAUGAUUUCCUUGAUUGGCUCUGUCGUAAAUCUUAUGAAUUCAUGCAUGAUAUCUGGACACAGUUUUUUUCAGCACAAAUUUAUUGUUUCAGGCUUGAUGGCUUUCACAGCUUUUUCUAUAACAAUGAUAUUGUCUUCAAUGGUGUAAUCAUUCUAGAAUUUCAUGAUGUUCUAUCAGUGUUCUCUUGCAUAGCUUUGAAAAUUUUUUCCAUAGAGUAUCAUGUAUAAUGAGCCUUAAAGGUCUUCAUGAUCCCCUGACCCUAGAGGCUGAAUUAGAAGCCUUCUGUUUGGGGGAAAGCAGACCACUUUGAUACCUUCAAUGUUGAACUCUUGGGUUUCUGGGUGACCUGGGCAUUGUCUAAUAUCAAAAGAACUAUAAAAGACAGUUCCUUAUUUGCAAGAUACUUCUUGACCUUAGAGACAAAGCAUUGAUGGAACCAAUCCAGACAAAGGGGUCUUGUCCAAGCCUUUUUGUUGUAAACCAGAAGACUGGCAACUCGUAUUUAUCUUUUCCCUUCCAGGCUCAGGGGUUAGCAGCCUUAUAGAUAAGGGCAGUCCUGAUCAUAAAUCUAAUUGCAUUUGCACAAAACAGUAGAGUUAACCUAUCCCUUCCUGCCUUAAAUCAUGCUCACUUCUCUUACUAAUUGAUGUCUUUUGUGGCUCUUUUUUUUUUAACUUUUAGGUUCAAGGGUACUUGUGUGCAGGUUUGUUAUAUAGGUAUUUUGUGUGUCAUAGGGGUUUGGUGUGCAGAUUAUUUCGUUUGUGGCAUUUUUUUUUUCCAGAUGAGGGUACUUCUGUUUGUAUUUAAAACCUGUUUGAGAAGAUAUCCUUUCUUCUCCAUGAUUUUUUUAUUGGCACCUGGGAACUUGGCUGGUGCCUCUUGGUCAGCAGAAGCUGUUUCUUCUAUUAUCUUGACUUUUUUUUUUUUUUUAAGUCAAACCUCUAAAAUUAUCAAAGCAUCUUAUGCUGGCAUUGAAUUAUCCAGCUUUAGACCCUUCACUUUCCCUUUGCUCUAUGUUGUCAUUUAAUAACUUCCCUGUUUUUCAAAUCAUAUGAGAGUCUGUAGCCUUUUUGAUAGCAAUCCUGUACCCACAUAAAAGCUGCAUUUUCAAUAGGAAAUAAAAAUGUAUUUCACAAAAAGAUUUUUGUGCCCGCUAGCGUAGCUGCAGCAAUGGCUUCACAAAUUUCCUUUUCUUUUUAACAAUGGUCCUGAUGCUGGAUUCAUUUAUCUUGAAAUGGUGGGCAACUACAGAUGCAGACCUCAGUCUAUGGUACACAUCAAGCAAUUCAUAUUUUUCUUGUAAUGUCAUGACUUUUCUCUGCUUCUUGGAAGAAAUUCCAACAUCACUAGUAGCACUUUAUAUGGUUCCUACCUAUGGUGUUAUUCAAGGUUUACAAUAUUGCACUAAAGACGAAGAACAUGCGAUAACCAUAAGAGAUCACUUGCAGGUUUGUUACGUAGGUAUACACGUUCCAUGACGGUUUGCUGCCGCCAUCAACUUGUCGUCUACAUUAGGUAUUCCUCCUAAUACUAUCCCUCCCCUAGGCCCCCACCCCCCAACAGGCCCCAGUGUGUGAUGUUCCCCUCCCUGUGUCCAUGUGUUCUCAUUGUUCAACUCCCACUUAGGAGUGAGAACAUGUGAUGUUUGGUUUUCUGUUCCUGUGUUAGUUUGCUGAGAAUGAUGGUUUCCUGCUUCAUCCCUGUCCCUGCAAAGGACAUGAACUCAUCCUUUUUUAUGGCUACAUAGUAUUCCAUGGUGUACAUAUGCCACAUUUUCUUUAUCUAGUCUAUCACUGAUGGGCAUUUGGGUUGGUUCCAAGUCUUUGCUAUUGUGAGCAGUGCUGCAGUAAACAUACAUGUGUCUUUAUAGUAGAAUGAUUUAUAAUCCUUUGGAUAUAUACCCAGUAAUGGGAUUGCUGGGUUAAAUGGUAUUUCUAGUUCUAGAUCCUUGAGGAAUUGCCACACUGUCUUCCACAAUGGUUGAACUAAUUUACAAUCCCACCAACAGUGAAAAGUGUUCCUGUUUCUCCACAUCCCCUCCAGCAUCUGUUGUUUCCUGACUUUUUAAUGAUCGCCAUUCUAACUGGUAACUCAUUGUGGUUUUGAUUUGCAUUUCUCUAAUAACCAGUGAUGAUGAGCUUUUUUCAUGUUUGUUGGCCGCAUAAAUGUCUUCUUUUGAGAAGUGUCUGUUCGUAUCCUUCGCCCACUUUUUGAUGGGGUUGUUUUUUUCUCGUAAAUUUGUUUAAGUUCUUUGUAGAUUAUGGAUAUUAGCUCUUUGUCAGAUGGAUACAUUGCAAAAACUUUCUCCCAUUCUAUAGGUUGCUGGUUCACUCUGAUGAUAGUUUAUUUUGCUGUGCAGAAGCUCUUUAGUUUAAUUAGAUCCCAUUUGUCUAUUUUAGCUUUUGUUGACAUUGCUUUUGGUGUUUAGUCAUGAAGUCUCUGCCAAUGUCUGUGUCCUAAAUGGUAUUGCCUAGGUUUUCUUCUAGGGUUUUUAUGGUUUUAGAUCUUACAUUUAAGUCUUUAAUCCAUCGUGAGUUAAUUUUUGUAUAAGGUGUAAGAAAGGGGUCCAGUUUCAGUUUUCUGCAUAUGGCUAGCCAGUUUACCCAACACCAUUUAUUAAAUAGGGAAUCUUUUCUCCAUUGCUUGUUUUUGUCAAGUUUUUCAAAGAUCAGAUGGUUGUAGAUGUGUGGUAUUAUUUCUGAGGCCUCUGUUCUGUUCUGUUGGCCUGUAUAUCUCUUUUGGUGCCAGUACUGUGCUGUUUUGGUUACUAUAGCCUUGUAGUAUAGUUUGAAGUCAGGUAGCGUGAUUCCUCCAGCUUUGUUCUUUUUGCUUAGGAUUGUCUUGGCUAUAUGGGCUCUUUUUGGGUUUCAUAUGAAAUUUAAAGUAGUUUUUUCUAAUUCUGUGAAGAAAGUCAAUGGUAGCUUGAUGGGGAUAGCAUUGAAUCUAUAAAUUACUUUAGGCAGUAUGGCCAUUUUCACGAUAUUGAUUCUUCCUAUCCAUGAGCAUGGAAUGUUUUUCCAUUUGUUUGUGUCCUCUCUGAUUUCUUUGAGCAAGUUCUCCUUGAAGAGGUCCUUCACAUCCCUAGUAAGUUGGAUUCCUAGGUAUUUUAUUAUCUUUGUAGCAAUUGUGAAUGGUAGUUCACUCAUGAUUUGGCUCUCUGUUAUUGGUAUAUAGGAAUGCUUGUGAUUUUUUGCACAUUGAUUUUGUAUCCUGAGACUUUUGCUGAAAUUGCUUAUCAGCUUAAGGAGUUUUUGGGCUAAGAUGAUGGGGUUUUCUAAAUAUCAUGUCAUCUGCAAACAGGGACAAUUUGACUUCCUCUCUUCCUAUUUUUAUACCCUUUAUUUCUUUCUCUUGCCUGCUUGCCCUGACCAGAACUUCCAAUACUAUGUUGAAUAGGAGUGGUGAGAGAGGGCAUCCUUGUUUUGUGCUGGUUUUCAAAGGGAAUGCUUCCAGCUUUUGCCCGUUCAGUAUGAUAUUGGCUGUGGGUUUGUCAUAAAAAGCUCCUAUUGUUUUGAAAUAUGUUCCAUCAGUACCUAGUUUAUUGAGAGUUUUUAGCAUGAAGGGGUGUUGAAUUUUAUCAAAGGCCUUUUCUGUAUCUAUUGAAAUAAUCAUGUGCUUUUUGUCAUUGGUUCUGUUUAUGUGAUGGAUUAUGUUUAUUGAUUUGUGUAUGUUGAACCAGCCUUGCAUCCCAGGGAUGAAGCUGACUUGAUUGUGGUGGAUAAGCUUUUUGAUGUGCUGCUGGAUUCAGUUUGCUGGUAUUUUAUUGAGGAUUUUUGCAUUGAUGUUCAUCAGGGAUAUUGGCUUGAAAUUUUCUUUUUUUGUUGUGUCUUUGCCAGGUUUUGGUAUCACGAUGAUGCUGGUGUCAUAAAAUGAAUUAGGGAGGAGUCCCUCUUUUUCUAUUGUUGGGAAUAGUUUCAGAAGGAAUGGUACCAGCUCCUUUUUGUAUCUCUGAUAGAAUUCUGCUGUGAAUCCUUCAGGUCCUGGGCUUUUUUUGGUUAGUAGUCUAUUAGUUACUGCCUCAAUUUCAGAACUUGUUAUUGGUCUAUUCAGGGAUUCAACGUUUUCCUGGUUUAAUCUUGGGAGAGUGUAUGUGUCCAGGAAUUUAUCCAUUUCUUCUAGAUUUUCUAGAGGUGUUUAUAGUUAUUUGUAUAGAGUUGUUUAUAGUAUUCUCUGAUGGUGGUUUGUAUUUCUGUGGGAUCAGUGAUGAUAUCCCCUUUAUCAUUUUUUAUUGUGUCUGUUUGAUUCUUCUCUCUUUUCUUCUUUAUUAAUUGGGCUUGUGGUCUAUCUAUUUUGUUAAUCUUCUCAAAAAACCAGCUCCUGGAUUCGUGGAUUUUUUGAAGGGUUUUUUGUGUCUCUAUCUCCUUCAGUUCUGCUCUGAUCUUAGUUAUUUCUUGUCUUCUGCUAGCUUUUGAAUUUGCUUGCUCUCGCUUCUCUGGUUCUUUUAAUUGUGAUGUUAGAGUAUCGAUUUUAGAUCUUUCCCGCUUUCUCCUGUGGGCAUUUAGUGCUAUAAAUUUCCCUCUAAACACUGCUUUAGCUGUGUCCCAGAGAUUCUGGUAUGUUGUGUCUUUGUUCUCAUUGGUUUCAAAUAAUUUAUUUAUUUCUGCCUAAACUUCGUUAUUUACCCAGUAGUCAUUCAGGAGCAGGUUGUUCAGUUUCCACAUAGUUGUGCAUUUUUUAGUGAAUUUCUUAAUCCUGAGUUUUAAUUUGAUUGCACUGUGGUCUGAGAGACCAUUUGUUAUGAUUUCCGUUCUUUUGCAUUUAGCUGAGGAGUGUUUUACUUCAAUUAUGUGGUCAAUUUUAGAAAAAGUGUGAUGUGGUGCUGAGAAGAAUGUAUAUUCUGUUGAUUUGGAGUGGAGAGUUCUGUAGAUGUCUAUUAAGCACACUUGGUCCAGAGCUGAGUUCAAGUCCUGAAUAGCCUUGUUAAUUUUCUGUCUUGUUGAUCUAUCUAAUACUGACAGUGGGGUGUUAAAGUCUCCCACUAUUAUUGUGUGGGAGUCUAAGUCUCUUUGUAGGUCUCUAAGAACUUGCUUUGUGAAUCUGUGUGCUCCUGUAUUGGGUGCAUAUAUAUUUAGGAUAGUUAGCUCUUCUUGUUGGGUUGAUCCCUUUACCAUUAUGUAAUGCCCUUCUUUGUCUUUUUUGAUCUUUGUUGGUUUAAAGUCUGUUUUAUCGGAGACCAGGAUUGCAACCCCUGCUUUUUUUUUGCUUUCCAUUUGCUUGGUAAAUAUUCCUCCAUCCCUUUAUUUUGAGCCUAUGUGUGUCUUUGCACAUGAGAUGGGUCUCCUGAAUACAGCACACUGAUGGGUCUUGACUCUUUAUCCAGUUUGACUGAUGGAUCUUGACUCUUUAUCCUGUGUCUUUUAAUUGGGGCAUUUAGUCCAUUUACAUUUAAGGUUAAUAUUGUUAUGUGCGAAUUUGAUCCUGUCAUUAUGAUGGUUAUUUUUCCCAUUAAUUGAUGCAGUUUCUUCAUAGUGUUGAUGGUCCUUACAAUUUGGUAUGUUUUUGCAGUGGCUAGUGCCAGUUUUUCCUUUCCAUAUUUAGUGCUGCCUUCAGGAGCUCUUGUAAGGCAGGCCUGGUGGUGACAAAAUCUCUCAGCAUUUGCUUGUCUGUAAAGGAUUUUAUUUCUCGUUCGCUUAUGAAGCUUAGUUUGGCUGGAUAUGAAAUUCUGGGUUGAAAAUUCUUCUUUUUAAGAAUGUUGAAUAUUGGCCCCCACUCUCUUCUGGCUUGUAGGGUUUCUUCAGAGAGAUCCACUGUUAGUCUGAUGGGCUUCCCUUUUUGGGUAAUUCAACCUUUCUCUCUGGCUGCCCUUAACAUUUUUUCCUUCAUUUCAACCUUGGUGAAUCUGAUGAUUAUGUGUCUUGGGGUUGCUCUUCUCGAGGAAUAUCUUCAUGGUGUUCUCUGUAUUUCCUGAAUUUGAAUGUUGGCCUGUCUUGCUAGGUUGGGGAAGUUCUCGUGGAUAAUAUCCUGAAGAGUGUUUUCCAACUUGGUUCCAUUCUCCCUGUCACUUUCAGGUACACCAAUCAAACGUAGGCUAGGUCUUUUCACAUAGUCUCAUAUUUCUUGGACGCUUUGUUCCUUUUCAUUCUUUUUUCUCUAAUCUGUCUUCACGCUUUAUUUCAUUAAGUUGAUCUUCAAUCUCUGAUAUCCUUUCUCCCACUUGAUCGAUUAGGCCAUUGAUACUUGUGUAUGCUUCACGAAGUUCUUGGGCUGUGUUUUUCAGCUCCAUCAGGUCAUUUAUGUUCUUCUCUCAACUGGUUAUUCUAGUUAGCAAUUUCUCUAAUCUUUUUUCAAGGUUCUUAGCUUCCUUGCAUUGGGUUAGAACAUGCUCCUUUAGCUCGGAGGAAUUUGUUAUUAUCUGCCUUCUGAAGCCUACUUCUGUCAAUUCGUCAAACUUAUUCUCUGUCCAGUUUUGUUUCCUUGCUGGUGAGGAGUUGUGAUCCUUUGGAGGAGAAGAGGUGUUCUGGUUUUUGGAAUUUUCAGCCUUUUUGCGCUGGGUUUUCCUCAUCUUCCUGGAUUUACCUACCUUUGCUCUUUUAUGUUGGUAACCUUUGGGUGGGGUUUCUGUGUGGACGUCCUUUUUGUUGAUGUAGAUGCUAUUCCUUUCUGUUAGUUUUCCUUCUCUAACAGGCCCCUCUGCUGCAGGUCUGCUGGAGUUUGCUGGAGGUCCACUCCAGACCCUGUUUACCUGGGUAUCACCAGCAGAGGCUGCAGAACAGCAAAAAUUGCUGCCUGUUCCUUCCUCUGGAAGCUUCCUCCCAGAGGGUCACCCGCUAGAUGCCAGCUGGAGAUCUCCUGUGUGAGGUUUCUGUCAACCUCUGCUGGGAGGUGUCUCCCAGUCAGUAGGCAUAGGGGUCAAGGACCCACUUGAGGAGGCAGUCUGUCCCUUAGCAGAGCUUGAGCACUGUGCUGGGAGAUCUGCUCUCUUCAGAGCUGGCAGGCAGGAAUGUUUAAGUCUGCUGAAGCUGCGCCCACAGCCACCCGAUCCCCCAGGUGUUCUGUCCCAGGGAGAUAGGACUUUUAUCUAUAAUCCCCUUGACUGGGACUGCUGCCUUUCUUUCAGAGAUGCCCUGCCAGAGAGGAAUCUAGAGAGGCAGUCUAGGCACAGCUGCUUUGCCGCACUGUGGUGGGCUCUGCCCAAUUUGAAUUUCCCUGUGGCUUUAUUUACACUGUGAGGAGAAAACUGCCUACUCAAGCCUCAGUCGUGGUGGACACCCCUUUUCCCACCAAGCUCAAGUGUCCCACGUUGACUUCAGACUGCUGUGCUGGCAGUGAGAAUUUCAAGCCAGUGGAUCUUAGCUUGCUGGGCUCUGUGGGGGUGGGAUUUGCUAAGCUUGACCACUUGGCUUUCUAUCUUCAGCCCCCUUUCCAGGGGAGUGAACGGUUCUGUCUCGCUGGUGUUCCAGGCACCACUGGGGUAUGAAGAAAAACUCCUGCAGCUAGCUCGGUGUUUGCCCAAACAGCCACCCAGCUUUGAGCUUGAAACCCAGGGCCCUGGUGGUGUAGGCACCCGAGGGAAUCUCCUGGUCUGCGGGUUGUGAAGACCGUGGGAAAAGCAUAGUAUCUGGGCCGGAGUGCACCGUUCCUCACGGCACAGUAUCUCAUGGCUUCCCUUGGCUAGGGGAGGGAGUUCCCUGGCUUCCCUUGGCUUCCCUGGGCUAGGGGAGGGAGUUCCCUAACGCUUUGUGCUUCCCAGGUGAGGCAACACCCCACCCUUCUUCUGCUCCCCAUCCAUGGGCUGUACCCACUGUCUAACCAGUCCCAAUGAGGUGAGCUGGGUACCUCAGUUGGAAAUGCAGAAAUCGCUUGCCUUCUGCGUUGAUCUCGCUGGGAGCUGCAGACCGGAGUUGUUCCUAUUUGGCCAUCUUGCCAGCCAGCCGAGAGAUCACUUUUUACUGUGAUAGGCAAUUUACUGCAGAGAGGAACUGUUCACACAGAGAUGAUUAGUGUCACAUGGUAUCGUGAGUAGAUACUUGCAACACGAGCUCAUCGCAAUAGCAACAGGAGGUGACCACAAAGUUAUUACAGUACUAGAGUUAAUUUUAUGCAGUUAUGAUUUAAUACUGUGUCUUUGCAUUUGUUUGUAUUUCUUUCAACUGCAAAUGGUACUAGGUACCGUCUAUAAGUGUUUGUGUGGGUAAGUGCUGAUAAAUUCUAACUUUUUAUAAUAGAUUUAUAUAUUUUUUAUGGUAGAAAUGAUGAGAUAGACUGGUAUCUACAUAUAUUUAAUGCAUUUUUGACGUACCUAACUUUUUAAUUUUUUUUAAGCCAUGCAGUUCAUCUGUGAAUUUUUUCAAAUUGUCACAAAUCUCCAAAAAUGUUAAAAAUAUAUUUAUUGAAAAUAAUCCAUGUAUAAGUGGACCCACACAGUUCAAAUCUGUGUUGUUCAAGUGUCACCUGUAUUUAGCUAUUCUCAAACAUACCUAUUUUUAUUUUAAGAAUUCCUUUCUAGUUUGAGUUGGAAAACUGAUGCUUGUAGUGUAAUCACUGUUGGUGACAGUGCAGUCAUACAAUGCAUGCAGAAUUUACUGGUUGGAAAGAUCAGUUUUUAGUUGAUUUUUUUUUUUUUGUAAAGCAAAACUUCUUAUCUCAGCUAUUAAAACUGUUCCACACAGUUGCCCACAGCCUGAAACCUAUCAAAUGUAGAAAAUAGGGACAUCACAGCAAAAUUUGGAGGGCAUAGUACAAAGAAAGGCGACAGCUGGUUUUCCCUUCCAAAGGUCAAAAUGACCUCAGGCUGGAGUUGCCUUUCUGCCCUAUUCUUGGUUUUAUUAAGUUUAUUUGGGAUCUCAUCUGCCAUGAGCCUGACUUUUGCUCAGGAAAGAGGCCUGAGAAUUUAAGGACUAUCUGUGAGUGGGCAGAGCUGAUGGAACUUUGUCUGCUAAUGUUUUCGGGUUUUCUUUGAAUUCUGUUCUUUCCAAUUCUUCACAUUGGCCUGAGUCUUCUUGUGAUUGCUGUGAAGAUAAUUAUCCAGGUCCUUUCUGAUCUUUCUUAUUGGAAAUUGGAACCAGCUCUCCUUGACUGUGACUCACUCGCUAAAUGUGUAAAGAAAUGAGCAGAUCUGAAACAAGAUUUUUUCAGCUGGAAAGAGUACACCAGAACUGUACACAGCCGUGAUGAGUUAUUGGCAUAGGUACUUAUUUAAAGAUUUUCUUCCACUGGAUGCUAUGCUACCUUGUGUGAACAGUUGCAUUUGUCUGUUUCACUACUUAGCAUAGUGUGUGGUGCACAGUAGGCAUGGAAUAAUGAUAAUAAAUGGAUUAAAUGGAUGCAUGAAGGUAUACAGGAGACUUUAAGCUAUCAUAGACGGUUCCAGGCAGGAGAAUAUGAAGAUGUAAUUUCAAGUACAGUUGUUAUUGUCAGUUUUGCUUUCCAUGGUUUCAGCUACCCAUAGUCAAUCACAAUAUAAAAAUAUUAAAUGGAACAUUCCAGAAAUAAUACAUAAGUUUUAAGUUGCUGAAUAAUGUGAUGAAAUCUUAGGCUGUCCCACUUCGUCUCGCCUGGGAUGUGAAUUGUCCUUUUGUCCUGCUUAUGCACGCUGUAUAUGUUACCCACCGUUUAGUCACUUAGCAGCCAUCUGGAUUCUCAGAUUGAAAACAGUGUGUAUAGGGUUCUGUUCUAUCAAAUGUUUCAGGCAUCCUCUGGGGGGUCUUGGAAUGUAUCCCCCAUGGAUAAGACUACUUGUAUAAUCUGGUAAAAUGGAUGAAUUAUUCAUAAAUAAUGUCAGAACCAGCUAUUUCAAACAAGAUUAGAUUCUCUAGCCUCAUAUCAUAUGCAAAGAUAAAUUAUAUAUGGAUUAAGGAUUUAAAUGUAAAAAAAGAAAUUAUAAGAGUUCCAUACCGAAAUGCAGGUUUAUAUUUAGUAAAAUAGUCAAGAAAGGUUUUUUUUUUUUUUUUUAAAAAGCAUAACAUCAAAGCCUAAAAUUACAAAGGAAAAGAGUGGAAAAUUCAUCCCCAUAAAUAUUAAAAACUAGUGUGUUGCAAAUAAAUUCAAAAGAUAAGGGAAAUACUGGGGAAAAUAUCUGAAACAUGACAGAGUGUCAUUAAUAUAUCAUGGGCUUUUACAUUUUAGAAAAAAAUGACGGAUAUCUCAGUAGUGAAAAGACUAUAGGAAAUGAAGAAGUAAUUCACAGAAAAAGGGUCAACUCCAUUUAUCAGAGAAAUGCAAAUGAAAUCAGGAUUGCAUUCUUCACCUGUCAAAUUGGCAGAUGCAACAGUAGCUGGUACUUACUGAGCCCUUUCUGUGUUAGCUACUAGUCUAAGAGUUACCACCACUCAUACAUAUGUAAAGGCUAAUGGAGUUGUAAAUGUAACUUUUGAGGACUUUAUUGUAUGUAUGCGUAUUAGUCUGUUCUCACACUGCUAAUAAAGACAUACCCGAGACUGGGUAAUUUAUAAAGGAAAGGAGGUUUAAUGGACUCACAGUUCCACAUGGCUGAGGAGACCUCACAAUCAUGGUAGAGGGUAAAGGGGUAGAAAGUCAUGUCUUACAUGGCAGCAGGCAAGAGAGCUUGUGUAGGGGAGCUCCCCUUUAUAAAACCAUCAGACCUGGUGAGACUUAUUCACAUGAGAACAGCAUAGGAAAGACCCGCCCCGAUGAUUCAGUUACCUCCCACCAGGUCCCUCCUACAACACGUGAGAAUUAUGGGAGCUACAAUUCAAGAUGAGAUUUGGGUGGGGACACAGCCAAAACAUAUCAGUAUGUUAUGGCCUUAUAUAAAAGUUGUUUUGUUUGUAAGCAGUUUGCCCUACAGUGUGUGGAAAGUGCAUCACUGUUGUGCUUUGGUUGUCCAACUCUUUGCUUACCCUGAUGCUUAGGUGUGAGUUGAUGGCAGUUUGGCAUUUGGAGAGCAGUUGCACUCCUAAAAUGAGUGAAAUGUUCUCUUCAAACUUGUGGCGUACCGUCUUUCUAUGGCUCUGUGACAGUUACAGAUCCGAAAAUUAGGUGUAAUGGCUUUUGAAGCAAAAAUCUCAUUCUGAAUAAAUCUCCCAUCUGUUCCAAUAACAUUUUAAUUGCGCAUCAAAUAUGGUACUUAUUUUUAAAAACUGCCUAGCAGGAUAGUUUGUGUUACUCUGCCUGUAUCCAUGACCGUGAUAAGAAAUGUAAGAAAAGGCCAGGCAUGGUGGCUCACACCUGUAAUCCCAGCACUUUGGGAGGCCAAGGUGGGUGGAUCACCUGAGGUCAGGAAUCCAGACAAGCCUGGCCAGCAUGGAGAAACCCUGUCUCUAUUAAAAAUAUAAAAAUGAGCCAGAUGCGGUGGUGCAUAUCUGUAAUCCCAGCUACUUGGGAGGCUGAGGCAGGAGAAUCGCUUGAACCCAGGAGGUGGAGGUUGGAGUGAGCGAAGAUCAUGCCACUGCACUCCAGCCUGGGUGACAGAGAGACAGACUGUCUCAAAAAAAAAAAAAAAAAAAAAAAUGUAAGAAAAGAGGUUGAGUCUUAUUUUCAUUUGUAUUUCUCUCACUGCCUAGCAUAGUGCCUUUCACUCAGUUGGAAUAUAUAAUAAAUGUUCAUUAAACUGA